ACCCUGGUCUCUCAGGACCGUUGCCUUUGCGGCUAUUUUUUGUGCAAUCCCCGAAGCCUGCGUUUCCUGCUGCCUGGGUUCGGGGCGGGGGCAUCGCGCAGGCCAGAACGGCCCCUGCGUCCGUAGGCCAGAGCCCCUGCCAUCAGCCCCUUUAGGGUGCUCGCCGGCUGUCGGGUGUGGGGGUAUGCCAGGCCCCGGAGGACUCGGCUUCCCCGCUAACCCGACCCGCCGCACCCCACCCAGGCCAGGUCAGAGCAGCCCACCAUGGGAUGGGGAGGGGGUGGAGGCUGCACCCCGCGCCCACCCAUCCACCAGCAGCCGCCGGAGCGCCGCGUGGUCACCGUUGUCUUUCUCGGCCUCCUGCUGGACCUCCUGGCCUUCACGCUGCUGCUGCCCCUGCUGCCCGGGCUGUUGGAGAGCCACGGCCGUGCCCACGACCCCCUCUAUGGCUCCUGGCAGGGCGGGGUGGACUGGUUUGCCACCGCCAUCGGGAUGCCAGUGGAGAAGAGGUACAACAGUGUCCUGUUCGGAGGUCUCAUUGGCUCGGCAUUCUCUGUCCUGCAGUUUCUGUGUGCGCCACUCACUGGGGCCACCUCUGACUGCUUGGGGAGGCGCCCGGUGAUGCUGCUGUGCCUGAUGGGUGUGGCCACCUCAUAUGCAGUCUGGGCCACCUCUCGGAGCUUUGCGGCCUUCCUGGCCUCCAGGCUGAUUGGGGGCAUCAGCAAAGGGAACGUCAGCCUCUCCACGGCCAUCGUUGCUGACCUGGGCUCGCCUCUGGCCCGCAGUCAAGGCAUGGCGGUCAUUGGGGUGGCCUUCUCACUGGGCUUCACCCUGGGCCCUAUGCUCGGAGCCUCCCUGCCCCUGGAAAUGGCACCCUGGUUUGCCCUGCUCUUCGCAGCCUCCGACCUGCUGUUCAUCUUCUGCUUCCUGCCAGAGACGCUGCCCCUGGAGAAACGGGCGCCCUCUAUCGCCCUGGGGUUCCGUGAUGCGGCUGAUCUGCUCAGCCCCCUGGCCCUGCUGCGCUUCUCGGCUGUCGCUCGUGGCCAGGACCCACCCUCUGGAGACAGGCUCAGCAGCCUGCGCCGCCUGGGCCUAGUCUACUUCCUCUACCUCUUCCUGUUCUCGGGCCUGGAGUACACGCUGAGCUUCCUCACACACCAGCGCUUCCAGUUCAGUAGCCUACAGCAGGGGAAGAUGUUUUUCCUCAUCGGCCUCACCAUGGCCACCAUCCAGGGUGCCUAUGCCCGGCGGAUCCACCCUGGCGGGGAAGUUGCUGCCGUGAAGCGGGCCCUCCUGCUGCUGGUGCCCGCCUUCCUCCUCAUCGGCUGGGGACGUUCUCUGCCCGUGCUGGGCCUGGGGCUGCUGCUCUACUCCUUUGCCGCCGCCGUUGUGGUGCCCUGCCUGUCCUCCGUGGUCGCUGGCUAUGGCUCACCAGGGCAGAAGGGCACGGUCAUGGGUACACUGCGCAGCCUAGGUGCUCUGGCCAGGGCCGCGGGGCCCCUGGUGGCCGCUUCAGUGUACUGGCUGGCCGGGGCCCAGGCCUGCUUCACCACGUGGUCCGGGCUCUUUUUGCUCCCCUUCUUCCUCCUGCAGAAGCUGAGUUACCCGGCACAGACGCUCAAGGCUGAGUAGCUGAGCCACUGUGCCCAGGCUGUGGGCACCAGGCAGAGUGGGAGCCUAGGUCAGGCCCCUGCCCACUGCCUGACCCCCACCCCCCGCCAGUCCAGGGAGACCCUGUGGGUGGGGGCCGGCCCCUAAGCAGGAAGCUCAGGCAGCUCCUCCAGACUUACUUACUCCUUCAGUGACUCCGAGCUGCAGCACUCCAAGGCUGUCAGGGCUUCUGUUUGUUUUUUAAACUAUGCACCAGGUUUCUGAUGAUGAAAUAAAGCACCUGUUUGUUUUA